AGCCAAUCCGCCACGUCUCCUUCUCCGGCCGCCUCCGCCGUUCCGGCCUCCGGGGUCGGAUCGCCUGCAGGUCGGUAAGCGUGGUGGGGGUGGGGUGAGGGGCAGCUAGAAGAGGGGGAGAAAAAGCAGUGGAAGGAGGUUUAAAAAAAAUGGUGGCGAGCCUGUUGGGGUUCCUUACCCCCUCCAUUCCUGGGAUGGGGAAGUAGAAUAUCCCACUGGGGUUCAGGCCUGGCCGCUAACAGCGUCUUUUUUUUUUUCUGUCUCUCUCUCUCUUUCUCUCCCUAUGGCUGAUUUUGGAAGCUGGUUGGGGAAACGCCUUUUUUUCUGCUAGAAGAAAAUGAUUUGAUUGAGGUUUUCACCCGUAUCUGUGUAGGGGAAUGAGUAUGUUGUUGCUGGGAUAGACCCUAGAAGCAGAAAAGAUUCGGUCCUUUCUGCCCCAACUCUAGGAGAAGAGGAAGAAUUCAGAGCUAGGGAGGAAGAGGGGUGAAGAACAAUCUUUCUGACCCUCGCUCCGGUUGAGUUGGAAAGUUCCGAAUUGAGGGGUCCACUGGGAGGGCUUGGGAGGGGGAUCUGAGGUUCCGGCGCCGAAGGGAGCCGCUCUCCGCCCCCUGCGUGGCCCGUGGGCGGCUCUGAAUGCUUUGCCCUGACCCGGGCCGGGGCUGUAGACUAGAGAGGGAGAGAAGAAAACCCAAAAGCAAUGGCCUGGGACUGCCGGAGGCUGGUGGCGGCGGGGCGCGCAGGCUGCGCACGGCUUACACCAACACGCAGCUGCUGGAACUGGAGAAGGAAUUCCACUUUAAUAAGUACCUGUGCCGGCCACGCCGCGUCGAGAUCGCGGCCUUGCUGGACCUCACCGAAAGGCAGGUCAAAGUCUGGUUUCAGAACCGGCGCAUGAAGCACAAGCGGCAGACGCAGCACCGAGAGCCGCCGGAUGGGGAGCCUGCCUGCCCGGGAGCCCUGGAGGACAUCUGCGACCCUGCCGAGGAACCCGCGGCCAGCCCGGGCGGCCCCUCCGCCUCGCGGGCGGCGUGGGAAGCCUGCUGUCACCCGCCGGAGGUGGUGCCGGGGGCCUUAAGCGCGGACCCCCGGCCUUUAGCCGUUCGCUUAGAGGGCGCAGGCGCGUCGAGUCCCGGCUGCGCGCUGCGCGGGGCCGGCGGGCUGGAGCCCGGGCCAUUGCCAGAAGACGUCUUCUCGGGGCGCCAGGAUUCACCUUUCCUUCCCGACCUCAACUUCUUCGCGGCCGACUCCUGUCUCCAGCUAUCCGGAGGCCUCUCCCCUAGCCUACAGGGUUCUCUCGACAGCCCGGUCCCUUUUUCCGAGGAAGAGCUGGAUUUUUUCACCAGUACGCUCUGUGCCAUCGACCUGCAGUUUCCCUAACCUGUUUCCUCCUCCCGGUCCUUUCGACCCCCGCGCUCCUUGGCCGUCUACUGGAAAAAUCGAGCCUCUCCCACCCUCAGUCGCAUAGACUUAUGUGUUUUGCUAAAAUUCAGGUAUUACUGAAUUAGCGUUUAAUCCACUCCCUUUCUUCUUCUUCUAAAAUAUUGGGCACUCGGUUAUCUUUUAAAAUUCACACAGAAAAAUUCCGUUUGGUAGACUCCUUCCAAUGAAAUCUCAGGAAUAAUUAAACUCUAGGGGGACUUUCUUAAAAAUAACUAGAGGGACCUAUUUUCCUCUUUUUUAUGUUUUAGACUGUAGAUUAUUUAUUAAAAUUCUUUAAUAAUAGGAAAAGGGGAAAGUAUUUAUUGUACAUUAUUUUCAUAGAUUAAAUAAAUGUCUUUAUAAUACCAAAA